AGUCUACUGGUCUCAUCAGUGAAAGGCUUGUGAAAAUUUCUGGAAAGAGCAUUGGCUGGCUUGUUCAUCUCUCUGUUUGGUCAGUUGCUGUGUUUCUGCCGGAUCAGAUGAGCAGAUUGGUUAGUGAAGGUCAGUGUGAGAAGAAGAUUGUUUCUGAGCUUGAGAAGCUUCUGGAGGAUUGAAGAGUAUUUGAAGUCUGUGUCAAACAUCCAUAUCAUAAGUGGAAUUUUGGAGAUAUUCAAAGAAUGCUGUCAGAAGGGUAUCUCAGUGGACUUGAGUACUGGAAUGACAUCCACUGGAGUUGUGCCUCUUAUAAUGAGCAGGUGGCUGGGGAAAAGGAAGAGGAGACAAAUUCUGUUGCUACCCUUUCCUAUUCCUCUGUGGAUGAAACACAAGUCAGAAGUCUCUACGUGAGCUGCAAAUCAUCUGGCAAGUUUAUCUCUUCAGUGCAUUCAAGAGAGAGCCAACAUAGCAGAAGUCAGAGAGUCACAGUGCUGCAGACAAACCCCAAUCCUGUGUUUGAAAGCCCAAACUUGGCUGCAGUUGAAAUAUGUAGAGAUGCCAGCAGAGAGACCUACUUGGUUCCAUCUUCUUGCAAAAGUAUUUGCAAGAAUUAUAAUGACUUACAGAUUGCAGGGGGCCAGGUGAUGGCCAUUAAUUCAGUGACAACAGAUUUUCCCUCUGAGAGCAGUUUUGAAUAUGGCCCUUUGCUGAAGUCAUCUGAGAUUCCUUUACCCAUGGAGGAUUCCAUUUCUACUCAGCCCAGUGACUUUCCCCAAAAACCUAUCCAGCGGUACUCAUCCUAUUGGAGAAUAACAAGCAUCAAAGAGAAAAGCAGCUUGCAAAUGCAGAAUCCUAUUUCUAAUGCAGUUCUGAAUGAGUACCUGGAGCAGAAGGUUGUGGAGUUAUAUAAACAGUACAUUAUGGACACCGUGUUUCAUGACAGUUCUCCUACCCAGAUUCUGGCGUCUGAACUCAUCAUGACAAGUGUAGACCAAAUCAGUCUUCAAGUGUCUAGAGAGAAGAAUCUGGAGACCUCAAAAGCCAGAGAUAUAGUCUUUAGCCGCCUAUUGCAAUUGAUGUCAACUGAAAUUACUGAAAUUAGCACUCCUAGUCUCCAUAUUUCUCAGUAUAGCAAUGUAAAUCCAUAGAGAGGAUGCUUCCAUUACUGUCUCGCAUUUACUUAAACAUGAAGCAACACUUUAUCCAUUUAUUCUGAGAAUGUGCAGGAGGGGUUAGUGAAGGGGAAUUAAGGGCUAGAGAAGUAAAGAUCAGCUGGAAGUCAUGUGUGAAUCAUGGAGAAAUCUCAUAAUAUUACACUUGAUGAAGGAAUAUGGUAAGAGGAGCCAUAAGGAAUGAUUUCAAAGAGAGGUGUGUACAGCAAGGAAGCAAAAAUAAAAAUGAUCAAAAAAGAAACGGUUAAUUCAUUUGAAGAAACAUAGGAAUUAAAAAAGAAGACAGUCAAAUGAGAUGAAACAAAAAGGCCAAAAGGUGGCCGGGUGUAGUGGCUCACGCCUGUAAUCCCAGCAUUUCGGAGGCUGAUGUGGGUGGAUUACCUGACGUCAGGAAUUCGAGACCGGCCUGGCCAAUAUGGUGAAACCCCAUCUCUACUAAAAAUACAAAAAAUUAGCUGGACAUGGUGGUGGGUACCUGUAAUCCCAGCUACUAGGGAGGCUGAGGCAGGAGAAUCUCUUGAACCUGAGAGGCAGAGGUUGCAGUGAGCCGAGGUCGCUCCAUUGCACUCCAGCCUGGGCAACAAGAGUGAGACUCCCGUCUCAAAAAAAAAAAAAAA